GCAUUUCGGGGCGGUACCAAGAUGGACUCCUCGCGGGCCCGGCAGCAGCUCCGGCGGCGAUUCCUCCUCCUGCCGGACGCCGAGGCCCAGCUGGACCGCGAGGGUGACGCCGGGCCGGAAACCUCCACAGCUGUUGAGAAAAAGGAGAAACCUCUUCCAAGACUUAAUAUCCAUUCUGGAUUCUGGAUUUUGGCAUCCAUUGUUGUGACCUAUUAUGUUGACUUCUUUAAAACCCUUAAAGAAAACUUCCACACUAGCAGCUGGUUUCUCUGUGGCAGUGCCUUGUUGCUUGUCAGUUUAUCAAUUGCAUUUUACUGCAUAGUCUACCUGGAAUGGUAUUGUGGAAUUGGAGAAUAUGAUGUCAAGUAUCCAGCCUUGAUACCCAUUACCACUGCCUCCUUUAUUGCAGCAGGAAUUUGCUUCAACAUUGCUUUAUGGCAUGUGUGGUCGUUUUUCACUCCAUUGUUGUUGUUUACCCAGUUUAUGGGGGUUGUCAUGUUUAUCACACUCCUUGGAUGAUUUCCGAAGAUCACCCCAUCCUGAGAUCUGCUGCCUUACACAGUGGAGGCUGUUUUCUGAGUGUCGGAUAACUCUGUUAUUAAAUAAGUGUAUAUUGAGAAUACUCACUCCAGAUGCUUAGGGGCAUGGUGAGAAGGACAAAGAUAGUGCCUCCUGUCAGGUCACUUACAUCAGAACUUGCAGGAAACCUGCUUUAUACAGCAGUUGACAGGUGUGGAAACUGAAGCUCAUGGAAAUAAAAGUUAAUACGCUAAAUUUUCAAGGAGUUAAUGAAAACUGACAUUUCUGCUAAAAACAGCAUGUUCUCCCUGUGGGAUUUUAAAGGAAGGUCAGUGGUAACUGUGUAAAGAAGAAAUGGACAUACUCUCAUUGUUAGCAGUCUGAAAAUAGUUGCUAGCACCUCCAUGCCCACGCCAAUGUCUCCAGCCUCCUUCAGGCACCUUGCUGUGUCUUGGGACCACUGGGAACCCUCACAGGAGGCCCUUCAUUCCUGUACACCUGUGGUGCCACAAGCGGCUUUGGGCCCGGAGGAAUCCUACACAUCUCAGAACACUUCCUCACCUGACCCUGUCACCCAUCUCCCCUUCUCGUGUUCUCAGCCCCUUCUUUGACUCUUGAAUUUUGAGUUUUUACAGAUGUUUGGGAGCUCUUACUCUGACAUGAAGUUAUAAUUGGUAAUGGAGACUCAGACAAUGUUGUAGAUUACAGAGUGAACUAUGCUUUUUAGUGUUAAAUGCAAUAGCUUGAGAUACAAUGUUUUACUUGGUACAUAAAUGCUGGUUUUCUUUCAGAUUUAAGGACAUACACUUUUUUUUUUUUUUUUUUUUAAGAGACAGGGUCUUCUAUGUUGCCCAGGCUGUCUUUGAACUCCUGGGAUCAAGUGAUCCUCCUGCCUCAGCCUUCGAAGUAGUUGGGACUACAGGCCCACGCCACCGUGCCUGGCUGGACAUGUAAAUUUGAAGUGAAUGGUUAAACAUCCAGCUAGCUGAAAGCAUGGCAGACCCUAACAGAAAAGCUACAGUGUGUUUUUGCAGCUAUGAAGUGAAUGGUUUCCUGGGGAAAAUUGUGACUUUGUAUAACUGUUGUUGAAACCAGAAUAAAUUAUAUUUCACUUGCAUAUGCAUAAAUUAUUAAAAUUUUCAGAAGUCAGUGAUACAGAAGUACUAUUUUGCAAUGUUAAUCUGUUUGAGUCUUUGGAGAAAGUGGUUUCAUUGUAGGUACAUAGUGCACUGUUAAUAUUUUAAACAAGUAGUUCACUCUUCCAUUUAAGGGAUAGCAGUUCCUUGUAUAAAAUGACUGGAUGUGUAUAAAGGAAUUAUGUUGUCAUGUGCCUUUAACCAGCUUUAGUAAUUACUAUAAUCUCAUAUUUAUGAUAGUUUUGUUAGGUGACAGGACCAAAUGAAAAUAUUUUAUGUUUUCUCAUCACUUUAGAUUUUAUCAUUAUGUACAUUACUGGGUUUUUAGCAUUUCCUAAUGUGAAGUUUUAAUCACUUUUAAGUAUACAUUUUUUUCUGUAUCAUUUAAAUAAAAUAUUUUUAUAACUUU